CUCUCGCAGCCCCGCCUUCCCUCAGCUUGAAACACCUGCUGCUUCGCGGCGGUGGCUUUGUGCCACUUUUCCCAGGGCUUGGGCAUCAUUCUGGACCCAUGUUCGGUGAACCGGUUACUCUCAGAGCUGCUUUCGGGCGCAGCUCCUGCUGCAGCCAGGGCCCGUUUUAAGAGAGGCUUCCAGGUCCAGCCCUCCCGCUGCAGCCUGCAGGGAGCGAGCCGGCCUGUCCCGAUGACAUAGACACUAGGUUUUUACAGCAAUUCUCUGAUGACCUUGAUAUGGUAGAACGCUGUGUAUUUCAAGAGUAAGCUCUCGUUUGAGGAGACUAACAAUUCCUGUUUUCGCCAGUGCCACCUGUGAUAUAUGUGAAGUUCCUGAAAUACCUAAGUCCAAGUUACAGCUCUGUCAUAUUCUACUGAUUAUUUGUUCCUGUACCUGUACAAGAUUUCUUCUUGAAUGGCAACCUAAAUGCCAGUCCAAAGAGGCCCCCAAUAGACUUGUUCACCCUUCAUGUCCUCAACUCUGGGGAAGUUAAGUAAUCAAGUUGAAGAAACACUUCCACUACUUAAAAAGGUACCUGCAAAUUACUUUCACAUUUGUUCAGCUAUCCUAAUGGGAUUUUCACUUAGUAAAUCUGCUACUCAGGUAUCUGCUAUACAUAUGGAUUCAAAAGUGGAUGAUCACUUAAUACGAGGGACUGAAAAAAGCAGGUUGGAACCAGCGACUCAGUUAUUUCAAAACACCAAGAAAAUAAGAUUAGAAGACACAAAUCAAGAAAACUUUACAAGGAUUGAAGGGACUGGCACAGGAUCUCUUUCUGGGAAAGCCUUGGGUUCAGUGGUAUAUGUCAAAGAAAGUGAUGGACUAGAAAUGACAGAUGUGGAAUGAAGCAAUUUGUACGUAUUACCAAAGAAACCAAAAACUGCCUUUGACUAAGGGGGGUGUUGAAAGAGAACUUAACCUUAUUAGGAAACCCUGACAAAAUGAUGGAAGACUAUUGCCUUAUUUUGCACUAUUUGUGAAUCAUCUUACACUGCAUUUUUUUAUGAUGCUUAUUCAAAAGGCAGUUGCUUUAGGGUGAAAAAGCCUUCCAAGAUUCAAAGCAGAUUUCUCUGGUAUUAUAUUAUAUCCUUCUUAAAAACCAGAGUUUUUAAGUAACAGUAUUUGAAUGGCAUCAAAACAUUUUCAUUUUAAUGUAUUUCUUUAACAAGUGGUUAAAAAAAGUGUCCAAGCAGCCGGGCGCAGUGGCUCACACCUGUAAUCCCAGCACUUUGGGAGGCCAAGGCGGGUCAAUCACCUGAGGUCAGGAGUUCGCAACCAGCCUGGCCAAUAUGGUGAGACCCCAUCUCUACUAAAAAUGCAAAAAGUUAGCCAGGCAUGGUGGUGGGCACCUGUGAUCCCAGCUACCUGGGAGGCUGAGGAAGGAGAAUCGCUUGAACCCUGGAGGCGGAGGCUGCACUGAGCUGAGGUCAUGCCAUUGUACUCCAGCCUGGGCAACAAGAGCAAAACUCCGUCUCAAAAAAAAAAAAAAAAAAAAAAAAGUCCAAGCAAUGUGACAUCCGUAUUUCACAAUAUUUCUGGUGUAUCAGUUUUGUAUGUUACAUUUCCAUUUUGGGAUUCUGCUUUAUGAUACUUUACUUUCUUACAUUUUGCAUUUUUGUUCUGUAAAAGAUCACUGCCAAUAAACUGCAAAAGACCAAUAAAUUGCAUAUCUUCAGAAGGA